AGCCCGGUGCGCCUUCACGCGCAGCCUUUUUGUUUAUGCGGCUAGCAGGGAGAGGGGCGGAGAGGCAGCGAACCUCUCAAUGUGCAGCAGGCCGCGAGGGCUAUAUAAAGCUCGGGUCUCGGACCUACUGGAACUGGUCAAGAUUGCCCGCGAGCUGGCAGCGGCCUUCCGCCCAGCUCUGCGGCGUCAUGGAGAACGCGGGAGGCGCAGAGGGUACAGAGAGUGGAGCUGCGGCGUGCGCGGCCACCGACGGCCCUACGCGGCGCGCGGGCGCGGACUCCGGAUACGCAGGCUUCUGGAGACCCUGGGUGGACGCCGGAGGCAAGAAAGAAGAGGAGACGCCGAACCACGCCGCGGAGGCGAUGCCCGAUGGCCCUGGAAUGACCGCAGCCUCAGGAAAGCUUUACCAAUUCAGGCACCCAGUCAGGUGAGUGACAGGCCUCGCCGAAGGUCUCCCGCUCCUCCAGCCCCAGGGAGGAGCCAGGGGCAUCGCGCAGCCCAGCUCCGCAGCUGGUCCUGCAGUCUCUCUCUCUCUCUCUGAAAAUCUGGCUUCAAGGUUACUUAUCUUCUCACUCAUCAAAUUGAAAAAGGUAGGGGCUCACGGUCCCACGUAAAGGGACUGUUGAUGAAUACAUACUCAGUGAACUUGAUGAAUAUAUUACGAAGAGGGAAAGGGGAUGAUAUGGUAAGAGAGCGGUGACAUCUUGUGCUGGCAAAACAGUUUUUAUUUUUAAAUCCUAAAGGGUUCGAAUGAAAUUGACUUCGCAUCAGGCAGAGUGUGUAUGCUGCUUUUGUCUUGCAAUCUGGAAGGAAGAAUGGGAUUAACAGUUACAGUCUUACAAGUUUGCCGAGUAGGAAAAAAUAGAAAUGUAAUGAAAAUCCUAAAGAUUAUUGAGAAUGGUUAUAGAAAGGGUCAAAAGUUUAUUUAACUUGCGGAGCUAGUUUACUGUUCCUAGUCACAGGAAGUCAGCCUUUAUCUAAGAUUCUGUGUCACUUUUAUUCAGGUGAAAUGUUAAGAAUUCUGCAGUUUUCCUGCCUCCGAGAGCUGUUAAAUGAAGAGCUGGAUGAUGUUUGUAAAGUGCCCCUGGUCAUAAAUAACACAUAGAAGUCAUUACAUCUAAUUUCCUACCGUGUGCUAGCACUGGUGAAGGACACAGGAAAAAGUAGUCACAGCACAUGGCAAGUGUUGUAAUGGAAUUUAGUUUGGUUAGUUUUACAAGUAUGGGCAGGGCACGAAGUGCCUAAAUCUGUCAGUGGUAGGGGGAAGGGUCAGGGAAGUGUAUAUUAUAAGUUGUGGUUACCUGGCUGAGUCUUGGAAAAGUUAGUCAGAUGAAUGGGAAGUGGGAGCAAAAGAAAUAGCAUUGGAAAAGAGAAGCAGGAUCAUGAAACGGUGUGGCUCCUUGCGGGAACUCCAAGGAGUUUAGGUGUGUGAAGUUGUGGUCAUUUUAGCAGGGUAAUCAGAGGCCAAAUCUUGCACACUCUUGUACAGAGUUCUGUCCUGAUCCUGUAUGUAGUGUUGGGAACCCAUGGGCUUUAUUCCGAAGGUAGUCUUGGGGGUUAUAUGUUAAAUAGGCUUAGUCAGGGCAUCAAAAGUAAAACUGGAAGUUCUGCAAUUUUUCAGGUAAGAAAUAAUGAUGAACCAUUGUAAGACAGUGGAAGUGAGGGUGAGACUGGGUGAAUCUAGGAAAUACUUGAAUGACAAAAUAGAUUAGGCUUUAUAACGUAUUGGAUAUGUUAGGUGAAGAAGAGGUAAAAGGCCAGAAUGGCUCCUAAGUUUGUGGCUGGUGAGCAGGUGAAUGCUGUACUAAAAGAAUGUAAAUUAGGGCCGAAAACAGAUUUGGGAGGUGAGAUCAUGAGUCAAGUUUUCCACUUAUCAUAUUUAAUGUGCCUAUGGGGCAUCCAAAGAGUGAUAUCCUGUAGAGAACUGCGUACGUAAGUUAGGGGCCCAGAGUCAAGAUCUUAAGUGGAAAUACAGACUUGGGAGUCCAUGGUAAAUGUAGGGUGGGGAAAUCAUGACAGUGGGCCAGGUCAUCCUAGUUUGUUUAGAGGGAGGGCUGAUGUUCUCAAUGAAAACCUGAGGGAAGGCCAGCAUCUAACCAGUACACAGAGAAAGAGAGGUCCACAAGGAGACGGAGAAGAAUCAGAACAGGAAGAAACUCAGAAAAGUAUGCGGGCCCUGGGAGAAAAAUGGCCCACAGUGAGAAAUUCUGGACAGAGUAUCAUAAUGACUAGCAUUCUUUGGGUUUGCCAGUUCCAGUUACGCAUUAGGAAAUAAAUUGUUUCUUAUAUAAGAAAUUCCUUUCUUUUCUGAAGUACGGUUACAAUUUAAUUGUUCUCUUAUAUUUUAUUUUUAUUCAUUUAUAUCUUGACUAAUAUGGUGUGUUUUAUUCUUUUUAUUCAGCUGUCAACUUUUUGAGGGUAGGGACCAUGAUUUAUUCAUCUUUAAAUUGUGAAUUAUGUUGGCACAAGGGAUCACUAAAAUAUUUAUUGAACGACUGAAUAAUUGAUAGUUACUUGUUUAAGCAUCAAAAAUAUAAACUUUUUUUAUGAUUUUUGCUGGAAACAUUUAUAAACUGCAUUGUUUGUUUUUCUGCCUUUUAAAGUGGAGCAUACUGAACAUAAUGUAAUCUUCCAUUUGUUGGGAUGACUCCAUUGUAUGGAUAUAUGGGCUGUUUACCCUGCACUAAAAUGACUGCACUGUACUUGGUGAUUCAGCCUUAUCUCUCCUCUUUCUUUUCCUUGAUGAAGACCAGAAGGCAAGAUUAGUAUUUGUCAGAUUUUUGAAAUUCUGAGGUAAUAAUACUUACAUGCCAGUUAUUUGUAUAAAACAUAUAUAAUUUCUCAACAUUUCAUAUGAUAUUCACAAAUUUAGUUGAAUGGGGAGAAGACAGGCACAUAGAAUCAAAGUUGAGGUCAGAAGUAGUCUUUCUAUGCCUCAAGUUGUGAGUGCAUAGACAAAAAUUUUAAAAUACUGGUUUUUAUACAUUUUUAAACUUACGUUGUCUACUUCUAUAAGAGUUAAAUCUGUGAGUUUUAAAUAAGAUAAUAGGUUAUUUCCACCUUUUUGUAAGGUGCAUAAUAUUUUGUCAUCUUUAUAAAGCUGGCUAUCAUUAAAGUUUUUAAUGUAGUGGUAGAACUCAAUUCAUUUUUUCCAAAGGAAUUUAGAAACUGGAAGACAAAUCUUCUAUAUAUUAUAAGAAUAAAUAUAUCCAUAAUGUACAAAGUAAGGUAAACAUUGAUCUUAUGCAUAUCCAGGGUUUAGUGUAAAUUUGUUUGAUCCAAUUUACAGCUUGAAUAAAGAUUUACAAUAAUCAAACAAUUAUUGAUACUUGGGCAGGUAGAUUCCAUGAAGGCUGUGAUAGUAGCAUAUUUUAACUCUGUAUCUUAAGGCUAUAUCCAAAUGUAUAAGUCAAUUGUUAAAUAUAUGGAGCUCUUGAAAUUUGACCAUUUCAUGAGUUUAAAGAUCCUGAAUGUGAAAAAAUAAAACAUGUUGUCUGCUUCUUUCAGACUAUUUUGGCCAAAAUCAAAAUGUUAUGAUUACUUAUAUCAAGAAGCAGAAGCUCUUCUGAAAAAUUUUCCAAUUCAAGCCACAAUUUCAUUUUAUGAAGAUUCUGAUAGCGAAGAUGAAAUUGAGGAUCUGACCUGUGAAAAUUAAUCUGAUUAGCUACUUUUGAUUAUAUCCAAAGCUUGUGGGGUUUAAAUUUAGUGUACAAAUGUAUCAUAAUUAUUUUAAACUAAUUUAUUUGUAUAUAAAUUAUUAAUAAAAUGAAAUAUUUUGUAA